ACAGUCCUAGGACCCUAUACAGAGCAUAAGCCAAAAUGGAAGAUGGUCCUGUUUUCUAUGGCUUUAAAAACAUUUUUAUUACAAUGUUUGCUACGUUUUUUUUCUUUAAGCUUUUAAUUAAAGUUUUUUUGGCUCUCCUAACCCAUUUCUAUAUCGUCAAAGGAAAUAGAAAAGAAGCGGCUAGGAUAGCAGAAGAGAUCUAUGGUGGAAUUUCAGAUUGCUGGGCUGAUCGAUCCCCACUUCAUGAAGCUGCAGCUCAGGGGCGCUUACUGGCCCUUAAAACUUUAAUUGCACAAGGUGUCAAUGUGAACCUUGUGACAAUUAACCGGGUGUCUUCUCUCCACGAGGCAUGCCUUGGAGGUCACGUGGCCUGUGCCAAAGCCUUAUUGGAAAAUGGUGCACACGUCAAUGGAGUGACAGUUCACGGAGCCACACCCCUCUUCAAUGCUUGCUGCAGCGGCAGUGCUGCAUGUGUCAAUGUGCUGCUGGAGUUCGGAGCCAAGGCCCAGUUGGAGGUGCACCUGGCCUCGCCCAUCCAUGAGGCAGUGAAGAGAGGUCACAGAGAGUGCAUGGAGAUCCUGCUGGCAAAUAAUGUUAACAUUGACCAUGAGGUGCCUCAGCUCGGAACUCCCCUAUAUGUGGCCUGCACCUACCAGAGGGUAGACUGUGUGAAGAAACUUCUAGAAUUAGGAGCCAGUGUCGACCAUGGCCAGUGGCUGGACACCCCACUCCAUGCUGCAGCGAGGCAGUCCAAUGUGGAGGUCAUCCACCUGCUAACCGACUAUGGAGCUAACCUGAAGCGUAGAAAUGCUCAGGGCAAAAGUGCGCUUGAUCUGGCGGCUCCAAAAAGCAGCGUGGAGCAGGCACUCUUGCUCCGUGAAGGCCCACCUGCUCUUUCCCAGCUCUGCCGCCUGUGUGUCCGGAAGUGUCUCGGUCGAGCAUGUCAUCAAGCCAUCCACAAGCUACAUCUGCCAGAGCCACUCGAACGAUUCCUCCUAUACCAAUAGUCCUAAGUGUUCCUGGGAAGAUACUUGGAAUGACACAGAUUGUUGUCUGCUGUACCUAGAGUACCUAAUGUAGAAGCUCAACAGCUUAGACUCCUAGUAUCUUUAAAUGAGCUCAGUCGAAGUAAAUCCCCCAUGAGCUAGAACACUUGAGGAGUGGAAACUCCUGGUUAGUUUAAUGUUCUCAUUAACCAAGGGGCAAGUAGAAACCAUUUAGCUUUUAGCUCUUGUUGUUAAGAAACUUAAAAGAACUGUGAAGUAGAGUGAAAACAAUAGGCUGUUUUUUGAUGAUUCGGGAUCUUCUUGUACCUAAAAGUCAACAUUCUGAAUAUUGUAUAGACACAUAUAAAUUCAGGUGGAUAAGAUUAUAACAAAUGUUAGGUAUUCCAAGAUAUGUUCUUGAUUUAGUUCCUUCCUUCAGCCCUUCCCCACUUUUUUUCUUUCUUUCCUUGAAUAAAUCUGGUAUAAUUUUGAUUUUUUGUAUAUAUAUACGUAUAUAUAUAUACAUACAUAUACGUAUAUAUAUAUACGUAUAUAUAUACACACACACACAUGCACUCAUAUAUUUAAUGUUUUCAAAGUCCUUAAUAUAUAUAGUUCAUAUAUGUUUUCAAAGUCCUUAAUAUAUGUAUAAAGCUUAUAUAUAUAUGUUUUCAAAGUUCUUUAUAUAUAAAGUUAUAUAUAUUUAUAUAGACUUUAUAUAUAUAUACAUAUAUAAAGUUAAGGACUUCAGAAACAUUGUAGUUAACUGAGGCUUCCAGUUACUGCGGUCCUGGUUGAUAAGAGAGACUUUGGAAGAGAUCAGUGCACCCAGAGGUUGGCAUCUAUUGCUUAUUGCUUCUGAUAUUAAAUGCUGUUAUUUGAAGUAAGCAGUUCUAGGAUUGAGAACACUGGGUGUCCCCAACAACCUGAACCCACAGGCAUUGUCUGAGGCAUGUUGCAACCCAAGCACUGGCUUAUUUUCAAAGUCAAGAUGCUCAGGGUUUUUGAAAUAAUUACAUACUGAUGCCAGCCACCAAAGUGGGCUCAAUGCUGGGUCAAUAUUUUUUUCUGUGGAUAGGGGCCCAAAAUAAGCACAAAGGUAUAUAAAAAGAGGCUUCUCCUUUUCUGUCUUCUCCUUCUUCUCAUUUCUCUCUCCUUCUGUCACCCCUCCUCUUCCUCUAUUCUUUCUCUUUUUUGUGAAUUUAGAACAUGGGAACUGGAUAGACUUUUAAUUAUUGUAAGUAUUACUGUCAUGGUUCAGUAUUCAGUUCUAAAAUGAAAAUUCCCUCUCAGAUCAUCCUAAGACUCAUUUCACACAUGUUUUUUUUUCCCCCAAUUUUUCUAGACCUUUGGCUCUCAACUGGAGACAAUUUUGCCCCACUCCCACUGAGACAUUUGUCAAUGUCUGCAGACAUGUUUAGUUGCAACAACUGGGGGAGAAUUGCUACUAUCAUCUAGACGGUGGAGAUCAGGGAUGCAGCUAAUCACCCUACAGUGCACAGGAGCCAGCAACAAAGAAUUAUCAGAUCUGGCCGGGCAUGGUGGCUCACGCCUGUAAUCCCAGCAUUUUGGGAGGCCGAGGCAGGCAGAUCGCACUGUCAGGAGUUCGAGAACCGCCUGGCCACUAUGGUGAAACCCUGUCUCUACUAAAAAUACAAAAGUUAGCCAGGCGUGGUGGCAGGUGCCUAUAGUCCCAGCUACUUGGGAGGCUGAGGCAGGAGAAUCACUUGAACCCGGGAGGCGGAGAUUGCAGUAAGCCAAGAUCACGCCACUGCACUCCAGCCUGGGUGACAGAGCGAGACUCCGUCUCAAAACAAAAAAAAAAAAAA